ACAGUGCGGAGACCGCAGCCCCGGAGCCCGGGCCAGGGUCCACCUGUCCCCGCAGCGCCGGCUCGCGCCCUCCUGCCGCAGCCACCGGUGAGUGCCGCGGUCCUGAGAUCCCCGGGCCGGAUGCGCGGCGGCCCCAGCUCCCGAGCGUCUGCCUCCCCCGCCCUGGGCUGCCCGGGCUCCCUGGGCUCCCCGGCGGCUGCACGGAGUCAAGGCGCCCCGUCCCGGGCGUCCCCCGCGGGUGCCGAUCCAGGCUGCCCGGAGUCCGGAGCCCAGAGAGGAGAGAGACAGCUGGGGAGCCUGGUCACCGCGGGCAUCUCCCCUGCGCUGCAGUCGCCCGCCUGGCCUGCCUUCCCGUUCCUCCGCCUCUUGCCCUGACUUCUCCUUCCUUUGCAGAGCCGCCGUCUAGCGCCCCGACCUCGCCACCAUGAGAGCCCUGCUGGCGCGCCUGCUUCUCUGCGUCCUGGUCGUGAGCGACUCCAAAGGCAGCAAUGAACUUCAUCAAGUUCCAUCGAACUGUGACUGUCUAAAUGGAGGAACAUGUGUGUCCAACAAGUACUUCUCCAACAUUCACUGGUGCAACUGCCCAAAGAAAUUCGGAGGGCAGCACUGUGAAAUAGAUAAGUCAAAAACCUGCUAUGAGGGGAAUGGUCACUUUUACCGAGGAAAGGCCAGCACUGACACCAUGGGCCGGCCCUGCCUGCCCUGGAACUCUGCCACUGUCCUUCAGCAAACGUACCAUGCCCACAGAUCUGAUGCUCUUCAGCUGGGCCUGGGGAAACAUAAUUACUGCAGGAACCCAGACAACCGGAGGCGACCCUGGUGCUAUGUGCAGGUGGGCCUAAAGCUGCUUGUCCAAGAGUGCAUGGUGCAUGACUGCGCAGAUGGAAAAAAGCCCUCCUCUCCUCCAGAAGAAUUAAAAUUUCAGUGUGGCCAAAAGACUCUGAGGCCCCGCUUUAAGAUUAUUGGGGGAGAAUUCACCACCAUCGAGAACCAGCCCUGGUUUGCGGCCAUCUACAGGAGGCACCGGGGGGGCUCUGUCACCUACGUGUGUGGAGGCAGCCUCAUCAGCCCUUGCUGGGUGAUCAGCGCCACACACUGCUUCAUUGAUUACCCAAAGAAGGAGGACUACAUCGUCUACCUGGGUCGCUCAAGGCUUAACUCCAACACGCAAGGGGAGAUGAAGUUUGAGGUGGAAAACCUCAUCCUACACAAGGACUACAGCGCUGACACGCUUGCUCACCACAACGACAUUGCCUUGCUGAAGAUCCGUUCCAAGGAGGGCAGGUGUGCGCAGCCAUCCCGGACUAUACAGACCAUCUGCCUGCCCUCGAUGUAUAACGAUCCCCAGUUUGGCACAAGCUGUGAGAUCACUGGCUUUGGAAAAGAGAAUUCUACCGACUAUCUCUAUCCGGAGCAGCUGAAAAUGACUGUUGUGAAGCUGAUUUCCCACCGGGAGUGUCAGCAGCCCCACUACUACGGCUCUGAAGUCACCACCAAAAUGCUGUGUGCUGCUGACCCACAGUGGAAAACAGAUUCCUGCCAGGGAGACUCAGGGGGACCCCUCGUCUGUUCCCUCCAAGGCCGCAUGACUUUGACUGGAAUUGUGAGCUGGGGCCGUGGAUGUGCCCUGAAGGACAAGCCAGGCGUCUACACGAGAGUCUCACACUUCUUACCCUGGAUCCGCAGUCACACCAAGGAAGAGAAUGGCCUGGCCCUCUGAGGGUCCCCAGGGAGGAAACGGGCACCACCCGCUUUCUUGCUGGUUGUCAUUUUUGCAGUAGAGUCAUCUCCAUCAGCUGUAAGAAGAGACUGGGAAGAUAGGCUCUGCACAGAUGGAUUUGCCUGUGCCACCCACCAGGGCGAACGACAAUAGCUUUACCCUCAGGCAUAGGCCUGGGUGCUGGCUGCCCAGACCCCUCUGGCCAGGAUGGAGGGGUGGUCCUGACUCAACAUGUUACUGACCAGCAACUUGUCUUUUUCUGGACUGAAGCCUGCAGGAGUUAAAAAGGGCAGGGCAUCUCCUGUGCAUGGGUGAAGGGAGAGCCAGCUCCCCCGACGGUGGGCAUUUGUGAGGCCCAUGGUUGAGAAAUGAAUAAUUUCCCAAUUAGGAAGUGUAACAGCUGAGGUCUCUUGAGGGAGCUUAGCCAAUGUGGGAGCAGCGGUUUGGGGAGCAGAGACACUAACGACUUCAGGGCAGGGCUCUGAUAUUCCAUGAAUGUAUCAGGAAAUAUAUAUGUGUGUGUAUGUUUGCACACUUGUGUGUGGGCUGUGAGUGUAAGUGUGAGUAAGAGCUGGUGUCUGAUUGUUAAGUCUAAAUAUUUCCUUAAACUGUGUGGACUGUGAUGCCACACAGAGUGGUCUUUCUGGAGAGGUUAUAGGUCACUCCUGGGGCCUCUUGGGUCCCCCACGUGACAGUGCCUGGGAAUGUAUUAUUCUGCAGCAUGACCUGUGACCAGCACUGUCUCAGUUUCACUUUCACAUAGAUGUCCCUUUCUUGGCCAGUUAUCCCUUCCUUUUAGCCUAGUUCAUCCAAUCCUCACUGGGUGGGGUGAGGACCACUCCUGUACACUGAAUAUUUAUAUUUCACUAUUUUUAUUUAUAUUUUUGUAAUUUUAAAUAAAAGUGAUCAAUAAAAUGUGAUUUUUCUGA